AUUCGCCGCUGGACUUUGACAGUGGUCAAAGGCUCUGCUCAGUUCUCUGUGCCUGUCUCCCUCCAGCACUGCCGAGGUUCUCUGCCGAGGCCAACCAGAAAUACCCCUUGGAAGCUGGAAUCCUGCAACAAUGGCCCAGGGUGUCCUCUGGAUCCUACUCGGAUUGCUACUGUGGUCAGACCCAGGGACAGCCUCCCUGCCCCUGCUCAUGGACUCUGUCAUCCAGGCCCUGGCUGAGCUGGAGCAGAAAGUGCCAGCUGCCAAGACCAGACACACAGCUUCUGCGUGGCUGAUGUCAGCUCCAAACUCUGGCCCCCACAAUCGCCUCUACCACUUCCUGCUGGGGGCAUGGAGCCUCAAUGCUACAGAGUUGGAUCCCUGCCCACUAAGCCCAGAGCUGUUAGGCCUGACCAAGGAGGUGGCCCGACAUGACGUACGAGAAGGGAAGGAAUAUGGGGUGGUGCUGGCACCUGAUGGCUCGACCGUGGCUGUGGAGCCUCUGCUGGCGGGGCUGGAGGCAGGGCUGCAAGGGCGCAGGGUCAUAAAUUUGCCCUUGGACAGCAUGGCUGCCCCUUGGGAGACUGGAGAUACCUUUCCAGAUGUUGUGGCCAUUGCUCCAGAUGUAAGAGCCACCUCCUCCCCAGGACUCAGGGAUGGCUCUCCAGAUGUCACCACUGCAGAUAUUGGAGCCAACACUCCAGAUGCUACAAAAGGCUGUCCAGAUGUCCAAGCUUCCUUGCCAGAUGCCAAAGCCAAGUCCCCACCGACCAUGGUGGACAGCCUCCUGGCAGUCACCCUGGCUGGAAACCUGGGCCUGACCUUCCUCCGAGGUUCCCAGACCCAGAGCCAUCCAGACCUGGGAACUGAGGGCUGCUGGGACCAGCUCUCUGCCCCUCGGACCUUUACGCUUUUGGACCCCAAGGCAUCUCUGUUAACCAUGGCCUUCCUCAAUGGCGCCCUGGAUGGGGUCAUCCUUGGAGACUACCUGAGCCGGACUCCUGAGCCCCGGCCAUCCCUCAGCCACUUGCUGAGCCAGUACUAUGGGGCUGGGGUGGCCAGAGACCCAGGGUUCCGCAGCAACUUCCGACGGCAGAACGGUGCUGCUCUGACUUCAGCCUCCAUCCUGGCCCAGCAGGUGUGGGGAACCCUUGUCCUUCUACAGAGGCUGGAGCCAGUACACCUCCAGCUUCAGUGCAUGAGCCAAGAACAGCUGGCCCAGGUGGCUGCCAAUGCUACCAAGGAAUUCACUGAGGCCUUCCUGGGAUGCCCGGCCAUCCACCCCCGCUGCCGCUGGGGAGCGGCGCCUUAUCGGGGCCGCCCGAAGCUGCUGCAGCUGCCGCUGGGAUUCUUGUACGUGCAUCACACCUACGUGCCUGCACCACCCUGCACGGACUUCACGCGCUGCGCAGCCAACAUGCGCUCCAUGCAGCGCUACCACCAGGACACGCAAGGCUGGGGAGACAUCGGCUACAGUUUCGUGGUGGGCUCGGACGGCUACGUGUACGAGGGACGCGGCUGGCACUGGGUGGGCGCCCACACGCUCGGCCACAACUCCCGGGGCUUCGGCGUGGCCAUAGUGGGCAACUACACCGCGGCGCUGCCCACCGAGGCCGCUCUGCGCACGGUGCGCGACACGCUCCCGAGUUGUGCGGUGCGCGCCGGCCUCCUGCGGCCAGACUACGCGCUGCUGGGCCACCGCCAGCUGGUGCGCACCGACUGCCCCGGCGACGCGCUCUUCGACCUGCUGCGCACCUGGCCGCACUUCACCGCGGUGAGUCUUCGCAGCCUGCACUACACGGCCCGCCGCCCCUCCGUCUACACAAGCUCCACGAGGCCCCUGCCCCCUGCCUGUAACAGCUGUGCCCGCACAGCCUCAGCCAGGCCCCCAACUUCCCGGCGGCACGUCUAUUCAGGAAACCUAGGCCCAGCCUUUGCGGGUCACUCUGCGGGCAACAUCCCUGAUCCUGUGACUUCUGCCUAUGCAGCCUCAGCUCAGCCCCAGACCCAGCCAGCCUGUCCUUUCCCCAGCUCCUAAUACCUCUACCUUUCCAGCCAAGGCAUGGACCCUGACACCUGCCAACAGCCCCUCUGCCCUCACAACCUCAGCCUGGCCUUCAUGACUUCUCUACCCAAGUCACAACCUGUCAGGCUGCACCACCUCAUCCUGGCCCGCCGAACCUUGACCUCACCCCUGCCCCUACCCGAAGGCCCUCUGUCCACACAACAUGAACCUAGGCUGUGACCUUUUGCCUUCACAACCUCUGUCCAGUCCUUAAUCCUGUGUUGCAAUUCUCUGUCCAGACAAUCUCAACUCUGAGGUUGCUUGUUUCGUCCCUGACUCCUUAACCCCUGAUGACAACUCUUAUGCCAGCACAACUUUGACCUGAUGACCUCAUCCCAGCCCUUGAUCGCCAUCACUAAAACAAUUUUAGAAUCACACCUGGACAAUCUCGUGCUACCUACAUACUGCCACUCCAUUUCAUUAAGCUAUUGACUAGCACAUCCAUCUCGGCCUAUAGUUGGCUUUGUCCUCACUCUCUCACUUUGGGCCACUGUCCCCUCCCUGAUCCAGGGUUCCACCACCAGGAGGGCAGACCCAGCCACAUACCACAACCACCCCCAAGCCUCACACUCCCUUGUCUUUUUCCAGACUGUUAAGCCAAGACCUGCCAGGAGUGUCUCUAAGAGAUCCAGGAGGGAGCCACCCCCAAGGACCCUGCCAGCCACAGACCUCCAAUAAAGACAGCAUGGAAACAAA